ACAGUCGUGAUGUCUUUCAAGAGGGAAGGAGACGAUUGGAGUCAACUCAAUGUGCUCAAAGUAAGCGUGAGCGGAGAGGAUCUGGAGCCGCUUCAGUCGCUCCCUGAAGAAAAGAAGAGUCGGGGACCUCCUAGCCAGUUACAUUCCAGAGGAUGAGGCGCUGAUGCUUCGGGAUGGACGCUUUGCUUGUGCCAUCUGCCCCCAUCGACCGGUACUGGACACCCUGGCCAUGCUGACUGCCCACCGUGCAGGCAAGAAACAUCUGUCCAGCUUGCAGCUUUUCUAUGGCAAGAAGCAGCCGGGAAAGGAAAGAAAGCAGAAUCCAAAACAUCAGAAUGAAUUGAGAAGGGAAGAAACCAAAGCUGAGGCUCCUCUGCUAACUCAGACACGACUUAUCACCCAGAGUGCUCUGCACAGAGCUCCCCACUAUAACAGUUGCUGCCGCCGGAAGUACAGACCAGAAGCCCCUGGUCCCUCUGUCUCCCUUUCCCCUAUGCCACCCUCAGAGGUCAAACUCCAAAGUGGGAAGAUCAGUAGGGAACCUGAACCUGCGGCUGGCCCACAGGCCGAGGAGUCAGCAACUGUCUCAGCCCCUGCACCCAUGAGCCCCACAAGAAGACGAGCCCUGGACCAUUAUCUCACCCUUCGAAGCUCUGGAUGGAUCCCAGAUGGACGAGGUCGAUGGGUAAAAGAUGAAAAUGUUGAGUUUGACUCUGAUGAGGAGGAACCACCUGAUCUCCCCUUGGACUGAUACCCUUUUCCCAUUCAUUCACAAAUAAAUUACAAUGGGUGCUGAGAACUUAACUUUCCUUAAGUCUGGUUCCUUGUUGGAUCUCAGGAUUUCAGAUCUGUUCAUUCUCAUUCCAACUACUCCUUGCCUGCAAGGUACACAGCUCUCCACACUCCUUUUUUUUUUUUUUUUUUUUUUGAGGCAGAGUCUCGCUCUAUCGCCCAGGCUGGAGUGCAGUGGCACGAUCUCGGCUCACUGCAAGCUCUGCCUCCCAGGUUCACGCCUUUCUCCUGCCUCAGCCUCCUGAGUAGCUGGGACUACAGGCGCCCGCCACCAUGCCCAGCUAAUUUUUUGUAUUUUUAGUAGAGACGGGGUUUCACUGUGUUAGCCAGGAUGGUCUCGAUCUCCUGACCUCGUGAUCCGCCCACCUCGGCCUCCCAAAGUGCUGGGAUUACAGGCAUGAGCCACCGCACCCAGCCACGGCUAUCCAUACUUCUAACCCCUCCCCCACCUCCUACCAAAGCCAUGCCAAGCGUCAGCUGCAUCAGCCUGGUGCCCUAUUAAUAAGACUGUCAAAAAGAGGUCUUUGCCCUUCAUGUUGUCUGCCUGCUUCUCCACUACCACUCAAAGUCCUUUCCCCCUUCAAAUCACAUAAGGACUGCAGGUAGGCACUAGGGGGACCUGGCCACAUCUGGAAACAGGGCUGUGGCUAAGUUCCCUGUGAAAGUAGAAGAGUCAAAAGGCAUUGGCAGGGUUAUGGGGAACACCAAGGGAGGGAACACCCCCACCUCCUCCUAGUAACCUGAACCUCCCUGCCUGCUGAUCCCCAGAGUAUAAAUAAUCCCCUGGUGAACUGGCAGUAACCCUUGGGGGUUAGCGCCAAGAUUCUCACCCCAAAGCCCAAGGAAGGAGGCAGGCAAAAUGGAUAGAAGGGCUUUUAUUUACAGGAAAGGAGGACAGAUGAGGAUUUAAGUGUCCAGUGCUCCCAGCGCUAGUUGGUAAAGGGAAAUGCAGUGUUAUCUCUUCUUUUGCUGGCGACCUGUAAAGGAGCAAUAUUAAACAUAAGUGUUUGUUCCAGCUCCUGCUUUCUGCAAAGGCACUCUUCUCCUUUCCAGUCCCUUAGCCAAACUCAUAAAUUGGUAGUGUCUUAGGCCACCUUACAGGCCCAUCCCACAUUAACAAAACAAAACAAGAAACCACACCACAAAUAAAAUUACGAUACCUCUAAACAA